ACUUGGUGGUCCAGUAAAAGAAUGCAUUCUCCUCAGCUAUCUGGAGAAGUUCAAGAUUGUCUUUGAUAAAAGAAUAUUUACCAGGUGUCUGAAAAUACCAAGCUGGAGAAUUAGUCUAUGGUGAUUAAAAACUCUCAAAGCAUGUCUUACCAACUGGAGAAUUUUUCCUAUGUCAACCAAAGGGGUGUCCAAGACACACAGAGCCACGGAAUCUCACAGGUGUCUGAGAAUUCCUCCUCCUGGGACUCUCAGAGGAUCCAGAACUGCAGCCCGUCCUCACUUUGCUGUCCCUGUCCCUGUCCACGUAUCUGGUCAGCAUGGGCUGAAGAGUUCUUACUCUCAUAGGAGACCUCCCAGUGCCAAGUGUAUAAGUGUGUCUGGAAUUGGUGGGUUCUUGGUCUCACUGACUUCAAGAAUGAAGCUGCAGACCCUCCUGGCGGAAUUCUCCACGAGUUUUGAGCAGCCUCGGUUUUCCCACCACCUCCAAAUCAUGGAAGACACAGGGCAGAGCCCCCGGAGCCAUGGCCAGCCCUUCCCGCAGCUCCGAAGCCACUGGCAAGCCCCGAGGCAGGGAUGGCCGGCCCAGGAGGGAGGAGGACGACGUCCCUCCCGAAGAGAAGAGGCUGCGGCUCUUGCUGGAGGGGGGAAGCGCACAGCCCCAGGACGGCGAGGACGGGGAGGACGCGCCGCGGCCGGGCAGGGUGGAGACCGGCACCCAGACAGGUGGCGACGGCAGAGGAUGAUGUUUUGUUCUGGGGUGCAUCACAAGAGACAAGGUUCCUGGCCGGGCAUGGUGGCUCAAGCCAAUAAUCCCAGCACUUUGAGAGGCCGAAGGGGGACGAUCGCUUGAGCCCAGGAGUUUAAGACCAGCCUGGGCAACAUGGCGAAGCCUCAUAUCUACCA